GCAAAAGCGCUAGGGUUGCAAGUGGCACCAGAGACGUGCCCUUGUCCCGGGGUCCAUUUGAGGGUGAGCGUGUUGGUGCCGAGCUGUUUUUUUGUUUUGUUUUGUUUUGUUUUGUUUUUGAGACCGAAUCUCGUUCUGUCGCCCAGGCUGGAAUGCAGUGGUGUGAUCUUGGCUCACUGCAACCUCCACCUUCCGGGUUCAAGUGAAUCUCCUGCCUCAGCCUCCUGAGUAGCUGGGAUUACUGGCACCCACCACCACGACCAGCUAAUUUUUGUAUUUUUAGUAGAGACGGGUUUUCACCAUGUUGGCCAGGAUGGUCUCAAUCUCCUGACCUCAGGCGAUCUGCCUUCCUCAGCUUCCCAAAGUGCUGGGAUUACAGGUGUGAGCCACCGCACCCGGCCAGUGCUGAGCUGUUUUGACAACUUGGACCCCGGGUCCUCUGUGGGUAGGAAAAUCAGCUCCCUCUUUGCUCCUCUGGGGCAGCUGCACCUCGGGCCAGCUUUCUGCCUGUCUGCCUGCCGGCACUGCUGGGUCGCUGUACCCAAACGCACAGCCGGUGCCCCGUGCCUAUUACCUGCCAGCCUGUCUGUUUCCCUCCAGCUAGAAGGUCUUCAGUUUCCAGAAGAACCAAAGCAUCUUUGGACCUACCUAGGGAAGGACCUGCCUGUGACCUUUGCCCUGUCCUGGAGGGUCCAGCUUUGGGCUGAAUGGCAGCACCCACGCUGGGCCGUCUGGUGCUGACCCACCUGCUGGUGGCCCUUUUUGGCAUGGGCUCCUGGGCUGCUGUGAACGGGAUCUGGGUGGAGCUGCCUGUGGUGGUAAAAGACCUUCCAGAGGGUUGGAGCCUCCCCUCAUACCUCUCUGUGGUUGUGGCGCUGGGAAACCUGGGUCUGCUGGUGGUGACCCUGUGGAGGCAGCUGGCCCCGGGCAAGGGCGAGCAGGUCCCCAUCCAGGUGGUACAGGUGCUGAGUGUAGUGGGCACAGCCCUGCUGGCCCCUCUGUGGCACCACGUGGCCCCAGUGGCAGGGCAGCUCCACUCUGUGGCCUUCCUAACUCUGGCCUUGGUGUUGGCAAUGGCCUGUUGUACCUCUAAUGUCACUUUCCUGCCCUUCCUGAGCCACCUGCCACCUCCUUUCUUACGGUCUUUCUUCCUGGGUCAGGGUCUCAGUGCCCUACUCCCCUGUGUGCUGGCCCUAGUGCAAGGUGUGGGCCGCCUCGAGUGCCCACCAGCGCCCACCAAUGGCACCUCUGGGCCUCCCCUCGACUUCCCUGAGCGUUUUCCUGCCAGCACCUUCUUCUGGGCACUGACUGCCCUUCUGGUCACUUCAGCUGCCGCCUUCCGGGGUCUCCUGUUGCUGUUGCCAUCACUACCCUCUGUAACCACAGGGGGCUCAGGGCCUGAACUUCAACUGGGAUCCCCAGGAGCAGAGGAGGAAGAGAAGGAGGAAGAAGAGGCUUUGCCAUUGCAGGAGCCACCGAGCCAGGCAGCAGGCACCAUCCCUGGCCCAGACCCUGAGGCCCAUCAGCUGUUCUCAGCCCAUGGUGCCUUCCUGCUGGGCCUGAUGGCCUUCACCAGUGCCGUGACCAAUGGCGUGCUGCCUUCUGUGCAGAGCUUUUCCUGUUUGCCCUAUGGGCGCCUGGCCUACCACCUGGCUGUGGUGCUGGGCAGUGCCGCCAACCCCCUUGCCUGCUUCCUGGCCAUGGGCGUGCUGUGCAGGUCCCUGGCAGGGCUGGUUGGUCUUUCUCUGCUGGGCAUGCUCUUUGGGGCCUACCUGAUGGCACUGGCAAUCCUGAGCCCCUGCCCACCCCUGGUGGGCACCACUGCAGGGGUGGUCCUUGUGGUGCUGUCGUGGGUGCUGUGUCUGUGUGUGUUCUCAUAUGUGAAGGUGGCUGCAAGCUCCCUGCUGCAUGGUGGGGGUCGGCCGGCAUUGCUGGCAGCUGGUGUGGCCAUCCAAGUGGGCUCCCUGCUUGGUGCCGGUGCCAUGUUCCCUCCCACCAGCAUCUACCACGUGUUUCAAAGCAGAAAGGACUGUGUAGACCCCUGUGGCCCCUGAGCCUGGGCAGGUGGGGACCCAACUCCACCCCACCUGUCUUCAUCGUGAGGCUGCCACAGUGCCUGACUACUUGUGGCCCAGGCAGGCUUCCCCCAACACAGGAACGCUCAUGGACACCUGCACACUCCACAGAAGACGUUGGCAUGUGAGGCCAGGGUGGGCACCAAAGACCAGGCCCAGAGCCAGGGGACAGGUUGGGGCUGUGGGCUUGGACCCAGGGCCUGAGACCUUUGUGGGAUUUGUGCAAUAAAGUGUUUUUAUUUAAAACCAAAAACAAAAACAAAAGCCUAAUGAAAACCUUAUAAGAAAUAUAUAAUGAAAUCAGGAAACUGGAUUAAAUAAUUUUUCAUACAUA